CUAGAAUUCGCCGCGCAGCUGCUUCAGCCCCUCAGCCCCAGCCGGACCCUCGGGUCCUCAUCCACCCUCGCAGGCGCAGGCCGUGGCUACCCCGAAGUCAACUGUGGAGGAUCCUUCCUGGCUUCCUUCAGCUCCAUCCUGCCCUUGGAUCUAGGUCACCCGCUUGGACCCAACUAUCUGAGGCCCGAAUGCCCCGCAGCUCCCGCUGCUCCCUCGCGUUCUGCUGACCCCCCUCCGAGUCAGGACAUCCCCUUUAGACCCCACUUUAGGCCCUUUCAGCCCAACUCCAACUAGCCCCAUCUGCCGCUUCCGCACGAGACAGAGUUUCACUCUUGUUGCACAGACUGGAGUGCAAUGGCGCGAUCUCAACUCACCGCAACCUCUGCCUCCCUGGUUCAAGCAAUUCUCCUGCCUCAGCCUCCUGAGUAGCUGGGAUUACAGCACCAAAAAGGAGACUAACUACCCAGCCCCGUCCAGUCAUGCAGGUGCAGGAUGAUGGAGUCAACCUCAUCCCCUUUGCCAAGUGUUCCAGGGUGGUCAGCCGAUCUCCACCCCCAAGGUUGCCUUCCCAGAGCCUCAGACCCAUGCCCCAGCGUUAUGGAGAUGUCUUCUGGAAGAACCUUAAUCAAAGGCCCACCCCCACUUGGCUGGAGGAGCAGCACAUUCCACCCAUGCUGAGAGCCACUGGUUGCUCCCAGCUUGGUCUGUAUCCUCCUGAGCAGCUCCCACCCCCUGAAAUGCUUUGGAGAAGAAAGAAGAGGAGGCCAUGUUUGGAAGGAAUGCAGCAGCAGGGCCUUGGGGGAGUCCCCGCCCGGGUGAGGGCUGUCACUUACCACCUGGAGGACCUAAGAAGGCGUCAGAGCAUCAUCAACGAACUGAAGAAGGCCCAGUGGGGCAGCUCUGGGGCUGCAUCUGAGCCAGUGGUGCUUGGCGAAGAGGGCUGUGGAUUCCCCAGCACCAAUGAAUACCCUGAUCUGGAAGAGGAGAGAGCAACCUAUCCACAGGAAGAGGACCGUUUUCUCACUCCUGGCAGGGCCCAGCUGCUUUGGUCUCCCUGGAGCCCCCUGGAUCAGGAGGAGGCUUGUGCCUCCAGGCAGCUGCACUCUCUGGCCUCGUUCAGCACUGUCACAGCCAGAAGGAACCCCCUUCACAAUCCCUGGGGGAUGGAGUUGGCAGCGUCUGAAGAGUAAGGAGAAACCACCGAUGCCGAGAGGCUAGUGGUGCCCCAGGGACCCAAGACUAGUUCCGUCACUAGAGUCACCCUCAUUGCUGACAUGAAGGCGUUUCCCCUUCCUUCGUCUCUCCAACUGCCUUUCCCAUCCUCUGAACUAGGCAUUAACAGCCCCCGUGGGCUCCCAUCUCAACCCACCGCUCUCACAGGAGCACCCCAAGUCCUGUUUUCCUCCAGGCCCCGCUCCUGGCCUUGUAUUCUCUCUGCUCUGUUAUUAAAAAGCAAGCAAGUGGA